GCAGCUUCUCCGUCAGGCCUUGGGCCAUGGCCUCGCUACGCAAUGCCAACCCGAGGCUGAAGAACUACUUCAAGGAGAACUACAUUCCUCAGGUCUGCGAGGCACUGUUAUGUGGUAUACUUGUUACAUGUCCUGAGGAUCCGCUGAGGUAUUUAGAGGGAAUGAUCAUGGUUAUAAUCAAAAGUGGUCUUCAGAAUCUUCUUUGGGAUAUGUGCAUUACUCCAUCAAUGAAACCAAACAUUCGAAGAUUGUCUGAAACUUACCUGGAACAACUUUUUGAAUUGGAUGAUCAGCUGAUGACUCCGGAAUUGAUGAUAAAAGCCUGUAGCUUUUAUACUGGACAUUUAGUAAAGACUCAUUUUUGCACUUGGAGAGACAUAGCUCGUACAAAUGAAAAUGUCGUCCUGGCUGAAAAAAUGAACAGAGCAGUGACAUGCUACAAUUUCAGACUUCAAAAAUCUGUAUUUCAUCACUGGCACUCUUAUAUGGAAGACCAGAAAGAAAAACUUAAAAAUAUUCUAUUGCGGAUACAACAGAUCAUCUAUUGUCACAAGCUAACCAUUAUCCUAACAAAAUGGCGGAAUACAGCAAGACAUAAGAGUAAAAAGAAAGAAGAUGAGCUGAUAUUAAAACAUGAACUUCAAUUGAAAAAAUGGAAAAAUAGGUUAAUACUCAAAAGAGCUGCUGCAGAAGAAUCCAAUUUUCCUGAACGAAGUUCUUCUGAAGUCUUUCUUGUAGAUGAGACUCUAAAAUGUGACAUUUCACUGUUACCUGAAAGAGCAAUAUUACAGAUUUUCUUCUACCUCAGUUUAAAAGAUGUGAUAAUAUGUGGUCAAGUUAAUCAUGCCUGGAUGUUGAUGACACAACUAAACUCACUGUGGAAUGCUAUUGAUUUUUCCUCAGUGAAAAAUGUGAUUCCAGAUAAAUAUAUAGUGUCUACUUUGCAAAGGUGGCGUUUAAAUGUGCUGCGUUUGAAUUUUCGUGGUUGUCUUCUCCGACCCAAAACUUUCAGAUCUGUCAGCCACUGUAGGAACUUGCAAGAGUUGAAUGUCUCUGACUGCCCAACAUUCACAGAUGAAUCAAUGAGACACAUUUCUGAGGGCUGCCCGGGGGUCCUGUGUCUCAAUCUGUCUAACACAACUAUCACCAACAGGACGAUGCGACUCCUGCCGAGGCACUUCCACAACUUACAGAAUCUUAGUUUGGCUUAUUGCAGACGGUUCACAGACAAAGGCUUACAGUACCUGAACUUGGGGAAUGGAUGCCACAAGCUCAUCUAUCUGGACCUCUCUGGCUGCACCCAGAUUUCAGUCCAAGGCUUCAGGUACAUUGCAAACAGCUGCACUGGAAUUAUGCAUCUUACCAUUAAUGACAUGCCAACUCUGACGGACAACUGUGUAAAAGCUUUAGUUGAAAAAUGCUCUCGUAUUACAUCGCUGGUUUUCACUGGUGCACCGCAUAUCUCCGAUUGUACUUUCAGAGCUCUUUCUGCUUGUAAACUCAGAAAGAUCCGAUUUGAAGGAAAUAAAAGGGUUACUGAUGCAUCCUUCAAAUUUAUAGACAAGAAUUAUCCAAAUCUCAGUCACAUUUAUAUGGCUGACUGCAAGGGAAUAACAGACAGCAGCCUCAGAUCCCUUUCACCUUUGAAGCAACUGACUGUGUUGAAUUUGGCAAAUUGUGUAAGAAUUGGUGAUAUGGGACUAAAGCAAUUUCUUGAUGGUCCUGCAAGCAUGAGGAUAAGAGAGCUAAAUUUAAGCAACUGUGUGCGGCUAAGUGAUGCCUCUGUUAUGAAACUAUCUGAGCGCUGCCCUAAUUUAAACUACUUGAGUUUACGAAAUUGUGAACAUUUGACUGCCCAAGGAAUUGGAUAUAUUGUAAACAUCUUUUCCUUGGUAUCAAUAGAUCUCUCUGGAACAGACAUCUCUAAUGAGGGUUUGAAUGUGCUUUCCAGACAUAAAAAAUUGAAGGAACUUUCUGUAUCUGAAUGUUAUAGAAUCACUGAUGAUGGAAUUCAGGCAUUCUGCAAAAGCUCACUGAUCUUGGAACAUUUGGAUGUCUCUUAUUGCUCCCAGCUGUCAGAUAUGAUUAUCAAAGCACUGGCCAUUUACUGCAUUAACCUCACAUCUCUCAGCAUUGCUGGCUGUCCAAAGAUUACUGACUCAGCAAUGGAGAUGUUAUCGGCAAAAUGCCAUUACCUGCACAUUUUGGAUAUCUCUGGUUGUGUCUUGCUUACUGACCAAAUCCUUGAGGACCUUCAGAUAGGCUGCAAACAACUCCGGAUCCUUAAGAUGCAAUACUGCACAAAUAUUUCCAAGUCAAGAUCAUUGUUGCCUCUAACUGUGCUACUCUUGUACUACAGUCAACAUCAGUGGCAUUGAAUGAUUAUGAACAACUGUGAACUGCAGUGUGUGUCCAGAACUCUGGUGUUUGGGAGGCAGGGGGCAGGAGGGUGUUGGAAAUAGGAACAUAAGAAUGCCCCUUCUAGACCAGCAAUCCAGCAGAAGCCAAGAGGGUUAAAGGACUUCCCUUCUUGGUGUAAGCUGCUGAAAUCUCUCGUUUGAGCUAUUCAUGAUGAGUUUCAGGGAGAUGCAAAGAAAUGUAAUAAACUCUUAAGUAACUUACUACCUUCUUAAACAAAAGGAAAAUAACAAAGUUUAAAAUUAUAAAUAAUUAAUGCCCUGAAGCUAUGUAAUAGAAAGAAAUUAAUUCUAUGAUCAACUUCCUGUAGAUGUUUAGAGGAGGAGAAGACUGGGUUUGAGCCAUUUCCAAGGAGGCUGGAUUGGUUUGGAGUUUUGAAAAAUGGAUAAUGUUUAGACUGAUAGAGAUGGGUGAAGGGUAAUGAUGGAGCCUUGCUGUUUGUUACAUGAAACUGAUGGUGCUAAUGUUAUAUGCCUCAACAUUUGGUAUUAUAUUUCAGUAAGUCUUAAGGGGAAAAAUGUUCAGAAAAUGUGUUGAAAGAUAUGAUAAUCUCACCUUUAUAGAAUUGAAAAGGGAGAAAUAUCAUUAGGAGAAUAAUGUGGGAAAAGCAAAAGAUAUAAACCCACUACUUUUGCAUAGUAAUGUUCUACUUUGAGGAUAUGUAAAGAUUAUAUAAGAGGUUUAAAAUGCAGGCUAGCACCUUAAAAAAAGAUUUAAAAAAUUAACAGAAUGCAAAACAUUAUCUUUGACAAUAAACUUACCAUUUUCAAAACUGAGAAUAAAUAUUUCUCUGAAGAGAAUAAACUUGUUUGCCAAGUUUUAGUCCAUAGGGAUUGGUGGCUCCAAACUAGGAAUUAGUAUAUGAUAAUUGCUUUUACUCAAUUUGUUCUUUAAGUUUGUAGAAGUUUUGUGUGAGAGCCAAUAAUAAGCUAAAAAGCAAUGUGCUUAGAGGCAGAAUUAGGAAUGCUUUGGUUACCUCCCUGUUAAGUUUGGUUACAAUUAUUUUAAUACAUCUAAAGUUUGAUUUAACUGAAAUAGCAUUUUAAACUGUUAUCUCUAUGUUGUUGGUUUUUUUUCUUCCUAUUUCAUUGCCUUACCUGAACUCAUAUGGCCAUUCAGCACAAACUUAACUCGAAGUGUAUGGUAAUGCCAGCUCCAUAUCAAUGACUCAGUUUCCAGACUUUUGCAAUUAAUAACUCAAGGUAACAUACGGCAAGAGUGGGGAAGGUAGUGCCUUCAUGGGUAAACAUCAUAGUUACUCAUUUCUAAUCGUACAGAAGUGGUCAAUUACUCAUCUCCUCUUUAGUACUAAUCUCGUGAUUCAAACCAACUUUCUAGGAAAGGAAAUUCUUCCUUCUGUCCUCAAAAUGGCUUUGUUUUCAAGUUAGACCUACUUUUUUUCUGAUGCAUUCUUUACUUUCUUGUUUCCUGCUAAGAAAGACUAUAACAGUAUUUUUUAAUACUGUGUUAUAGUGUUGUGACACCUUUGAGUCACAAACCUUCUCAUAAAAAUGUGUAUUAUAGACAAAACUGCAUGAACUUUCAGGGAGUUCAUGGACCUCCCUGAAGUUCAUCCAUGUAGUCAAAAGGGAUCUGUGAACUCUGGGUUAAGAGCUCCUGGCCUGGUGCAUGGUCAGCCUUCACAGGUAGGCUGGUUAGGUUACUCCCUCAUCAGAGAAACUAGAAAUACCAAGGAAGGGGCUUACUUAAAGCAGUAUAAAUAAAUAGAGGCCUCAGUGUUCCUCUUCCAUGGCCAUGUGUAGUUUCCUUACCCAUUCACUGUAUCUGUUAAUUUCUGAACUGGCUGAAUCAGAGUUACUGAGGCUUUGGGACCCUGUUUAUUUGUACACUUACCCAUAUCCUCACUCUCAGCAAGGCAAGAGAGGUCUCAUGUGAAUUCAGAUUGUGACAGUGAAUUCCCUAACUCCAAAUUUGGUUGAGUUUGAAAAUUUUGCACUAGGGGUUACUUCUGCAACUAGCUAAUGCUAAGCACUGUUAUUACAGGAAGGCAGCUCAAAGAAUGUCAUCUAAAGUUCAGCAGCAGGAAUACAACACUAAUGACCCUCCACGUUGGUUUGGCUAUGAUAGGGAAGGAAACCCUGUUACAGAGCUUGACAACAUAACAUCAUCUAAAGGAGCCUUAGAAUUAACAGUGAAAAAGUCAACAUACAGCAGUGAAGACCAAGCAGCGUGACCUUCAGCCUCAAGCAGGAAGAACAAAAAAUCAAGAACUUGGCAAGUUUUCUCCAUUUGUUGCAAGUAUGUUUACUAGCUGAAUCUCAAUAACAAUGUAAACAAGCAACAAACCAUCUUCUGAUUCUUAUUCCAACUACAAAUAUUUCCAAACACAUCAGUAGUUCUUCUGUCUAAAUAAUCAUGAUUUAAAAAAGAAGCCAGGCCAGGAGCGGUGGCUCACACCUGUAAUCCUAGCACUUUGGUAGGCCAAGGCGGGUGGACCAUAAGUCAGGAGUUCAAGACCAGCCUGGCCAACAUGGUGAAACCCCAUCUUUACUAAAAAUACAAAAAUUAGCCGGGUGUGGUGGUGGGCGCCUGUAAUCCCAGCUACUCAGGAGGCUGAGGCAGGGGACUUGCUUGAACCUGAGAGGCGGAGGUUGCAGUGAGCCUAGAUCACGUCACUGCAUUCCAGCCUCGGCGACAGAGCAAGACUCCGUCUCAAAAAAAAAAAAAAAAAAAAGAAGCCAAAUCAAGUACUGACUACACAAAAUUUCUGCCUAAAUUUAAUCAAACCAAUAGUUUUGAUGAGAUUAUAAAAUCUACAGUUAUAUGAAACAACCCUGAGAGAUGAGACUUUUUUGACAAGAAAUUAAGAAAUUUUUCUUUAGAAAGGAAAAAGAAAGCAGAGAUGGCCAUAUGUCAAACUAAGAGUUUGAGCCAGGGGAAUAACUUUAAGGAUCUGUAACGCUUUUUAAGGCUUUAUAAAGAAUACAGACAUAUAUUAAUAUUUUCAAAGGAAAUGUGGCUUUUCUGUGGUUUCCAGACAUUUAACAACAAAAGAGAACUAAAUGCCGCCAAUUAACUCUGUACUUAUCUCAACAUUUGACUUAGUCAGGGGCAAAUUAAAUAGAAACAAGAACUAUCUGAAUAGAAAGAAUGUCCCUGCAAUGUCUCAGAAAGACAUCUCUUUAAUCAAAUUUGCACAACGGAGGAAUUCUUAAACUAUGCUAUGCCAAAAAAGAUGCUCCCUCAAUUUUAUGCUAGGAAGUAUGGGUUAUUAAUUGCAUAUCUACAUAUUAGUUUUUAAUAAGCUUUAAUCCGUAGGUUUUAGUAUAUGUGCUGCCGAAGUGAGCACAUCUGUGGGUUUUUACCAUUAUUUGAUAUUAUGUAACACUGAUGUUGACACAGUCCAAGAGAAAACACAACUCUGUUCUGACUGCCGCAAACAAGCCUUGUCAGCAAUAUCAGAUCAGCCUUUUAACCUUUCUAUUUCCUCAAUUACUUAUCUCUCACGUGGAGUUAAUUCUCUUUUUGUAUCCCACAAGUUUCAAAUAAGGAUUAAAAACUUAAGAUAAAGCAUCGUUAUUUUGAAAAGUUUUAAAAAGAUUGUACAAAGUAUUAUUAUAGGCUACCUUGUAUUAGCUAAAUGCUUUUAGUAAUUCUCCCCCACUGAGGUUGACUUGCAAAGUUUUUGAAAUAAGGUAAUAUUACUUAGCUGUGGAAAGGUUCCUAGGAGUGGGCACACAGGCAACAGAAUCAUUUGAGUGGGAAGUUUUAGACCAUAGCCAAGAGACAUAAGAUGACAUAAGAGUAUGAUUUUAACCUAAAUUUGGAAAUUUCUGGCAGCUGCAUUAAAGAUGUUUUCAAAAAUCUGAUCCCUAAGUGCUUCAUGCACACAACUGGUGGAACUUAUAAAAGAGGCAAUUGCUUUCUAAAGGAAUGACACCUGCACUGGUUAGACCCCGGUAAGAAACACACCCUGUUAUGUUCUCCAGAAACCUAGCAGGUUGCUUUACAUUCAGAGCUUGCUCCAAAGCUCUUUGAGUAACAUCCUUUCUUAAACAAGAACAGAAGACACAUUCAUUCAUUCUGGGGAGACAAAUUUUACAGCUACAUAAAUGAAGAAAAGGAGUAGAAAAAGUGAGCUAUGAAAGGAGACCAAGAAUAGGGAUACAGGUAGAGAAAUCUUUUAAGUUUUCGAUGCAAACUACUCAAAAUAUCAAAGAUAUUAGUUAGGUCUUUAGCCCUUACGUAUUUCAUAUUCAUAGGUCUGUGUCCAAGAGAGUAAAUUAUGGCAGCUUUUUCUUUUUGUCUGGGACUUAACAAUGUGAUCCAAAUAUGUACAAUUCCAUUAGUAGCUUUAAAUAUAGUUGACUGCUGUUAUGCUUAUGA